CUUUUUUUCUGUAUUUAUCAGUUGUGGUUCUUCUAUAAAGAAGAUUUUCCAUCAAUUUUUUGGUUACUUUGAAAUACAAGAAGAGCAGGAUACAUGCUUAUUUCUUUUAUCAAUUUGUAGAAUAAGUUGUCUUUGCAGUAAGGCUUAUUUUUACUAUUUAUAGGAGUAGAAGCAGUUUGAGGCUUUUAAUUUUUUAAGAGAAGCUUUAAAAAAUGAAGUAUAACUUACAUACAAUAAAAUACAUAAAUCUUAAAUGAUGUACUCUUGGUGAAUUUUACACCAUCCAGAUCAAGUUGCCAAUGUCUCAGUCAACCCCUUUUCAGUUAGCCCGCUCUUGCAGAGUUAGUCUCUGUCCCAGGGAUUUCCAACGUAUGAAUUCCAGAUCGGCAGAAUCAACAUCACCUGGAAACUUGUUAAAAAUACUUUUUCCUAAGGCCUUACCUUUGAUAUGUUGGUUCAGAAACUCUGGGAGUGGAGUCCAGAGAUCUUGUUUUAAUGAAGUCUUCCGGGUGAUUCUGAUACACACAAGCACUGUGGAACCACUGCUGUAUUCUAACACAUAUUAUCAUAAUUACUUUAAUCAGUUCUUGACCUUACUCUCACAUAAAUGGAUCAACUGAACAUUUCUCCCAUUCCAUUCUGUUUCCUCCACAUGCACUGGAUUUUUUUCCUGUGCCCCUGGGUGAGAAGUCUUGCUGCUGCUUCCCCAGCAGUUUAAGGCUUUUGCUUCAGAGGACAGAAGGAGGCAGGGAAGUGAGAGGGUUUGUGUUUGUUCCAGUGCAGGCUUUCAUCACCUCCUGCAUGCCUGUGCCGUUAAGAGGGGGCUUUCUUAUAUGUUUCUCUUGAAUGCUAGGUUGAGGCCCAUGAGGAAGAGCUUGCUGUUGUGCUAGUCCACAUUUGGCUUUUAAGCAGACAUUAAAAUGUUAGCUUAUUACUCCUUUUUAUGGUGGUCAUUUCUGUCUUUUAUGCUCAGCCAAAAGUGAAACUGUUAAAUGUCCCGUCUCUCCUGGGAGGGGCUUGUCUCCCUUUGGAAUUUGGUUGACUUGCUUGCCUUACAAUAACAGCUUUCUGAUGGGCUUAUGAAAGGUUAUGAUUUUGAAGAUUAUCUGGCUCUUCCAGGUUUUUAGGUAGGAGUGAUAUUAAUUGCAGCUUUUUACAUCGAAAAUGGAAAUCUGACCUUCAUAUAAAUGGAAUCACACUAUAUUUAUCCUCAAGUCUCUGGAUUCUCUUGUUUAAAGGAUCCUGUUAGUUUUAUCUGUAUUGUUGCAUAUAGCAAUAAUUAGGUCUUCAUUACCAUGUUGUAUUCUAUUAUGUAGAAACUACCACUAACAUUUUUCUUUUUUUUUUUUGAGAUGGAGUUUCGCUCUUGUUGUCCAGGCUAGAGUGCAGUGGUGCAAUCUCACCUCACUGCAACCUCUGCGUUUUGGAUUUUUGGAUUCUCCUGCCUCAGCCUCCCGAGUAGCUGGGAUUACAGGCAUGCACCACCAUGCCUGGCUAAUUUUGUAUUUUGAGUAGAGACAGGGUUUCUCCACAUUGGUCAGGCUGGUCUUGAACUCCCGACCUCAGGUGAUCCGCCCACCUCGGCCUCCCAAAGUGCUGGGAUUACAGGCGUGAGCCACCGUGCCUGGCCUCACUAACAUUUUUCUAUGAAACUAUAAUUCUAACGUAUGUAGAUGUUUACAAAAUGUUUCAUGUUUAGGUAUUUACUGUUUGUCAUAUACUGAGCAAGCUGGGGCUUGAGUAGUGUAUUCUGGUGAAUCAAACCCAGUAUGUGCCAUUAGUGAAUUUAUGGCCUAGUAGUCUUCCAUCCAUGUUAAUGUUACUCCUGUUACUGUUCUUCCUGAUGCUGGAUCUCCUAUGGCCCUGUCCCUACUGCCCAUUUAAUUUAAUAUAGGGAACUUUGCUCAAGCAGAUCCUGUAUAGACUGAAAUGUUAAAUGUUUGCUUGUUUUGAUUUGACCUGGUGUUUGUAAAAUGUCUGUACUUAAUUGUUAUAGGUGUCUACUAUUUUAAAAGGCAGUAUAUGGGUCAAUAUUGACGUAGUUUGGCAUGUGUCAUCUUUUCCUAGCCCUCUGCACAUUAAUGACAUUUGCAUGCCCCACAGGUAUUUGAGUUUUGUGUUCCUGUACCAACUGGUAAAAUUUGGAGGGAGAAAUUUUUAUGGUUUGGCCAGGGGAACUUCUGGUUCCUCUUGUUAGUAUUUUUGUUCUUUUAAGUUUAAAUUUCAGGAAGUAAUAUACAUUGGAUCUGCAUAAUAACCUUAUUUAAUGUUCUUAAACCACAAAUUCCUUUUGAGCUUAACUUUUACAAGUUACUUUGAACUCCAUUUAUGUGAGUGAAAAUGAAGUUGUAGCUGGAGCACAGAAAGGUCAUAUUGAUACAAUAAAGAGGCUUUGUGUUGAGCAUGGCAUGUCCUCUUUAAAACUUUGAAGAAUCUGGAAGUAAGCGCACCAUUUUAAACCUUUACUUUGGCUAAAGUUGUCAUUUUUGCUUAUUUAAUUGGUAUUUUAUUUUAUUUUAUUUUAAUUUAUUUUAUUUUAUUUUUGAGAUGGAGUUUCACUCUUGUCACCCAGGCUGGAGUGCAAUGGCGCAAUCUCCGGUCACUGCAACCUCUGCCUUCUGGGUUCAAGCAAUGCUUUAGCCUCAGCCUCCCAAGUAGCUAGAAUUACAGGUGCCUGCCACCACGCCCAGCUAAUUUUUUUUUUUUUUUGUAUUUUUAGUAGAGAUGGGGUUUUACCAUGUUGGCCAGGCUGGUCUCAAACUCCUGACCUCAGGUGAUCCACCCGCCUUGGCCUCCCAAAGUGCUGGGAUUACAGGUGUGAGCCACCACACCCAGCUAUUUUUUUUUUUUUUUUUUGUAUUUUUAGUAGAGAUGGGGUUUUACCAUGUUGGCCAGACUGGUCUCAAACUCCUGACCUCAGGUGAUCCACCUGCCUGGGCCUCCCAAAGUGCUGGGAUUACAGGUGUGAGCCACCACGCCUGGCCACUUAUUUAAUUGCUAUAAUCAAGCCUUUGAAUCAGCUUAUGCCACAGAUGACAGCCAGGAAAAAAUGGGAAAAGGGGAUAUGAAAGAAGUAGUUGAGUAACACAAGGUUAAAAAAAAUUACUUUAAAUUCUGAUCUAGUUGUCUGAACUUGAAAGCAGAUUUCCGAAGUAACUGCUUAUACGUGUGUAGUCAUCAGUAUUGUUGUUCAGUUAAUUGCUCUUGUACUUAGUAGUGAGUUUAUGUCUGUUUAAACCCCUAAAAUGCAGACAAUUUAUACCUUCUAAAAAACUAUUUGAAAAACUAAAAAAAGACAGUGAGUGGGUGGUUCCUCAGAUGAUGAGGUAAUGGAUAUGAAAGGAGUUUGAAAAAGUGACAGCUCUUACUGUUCUUCUGCUAAAUUUCUGUAAUUAAUAUCUAGGUCCUUUGCAGUCUUUAUGGUUUUCCUCUGACAUUAGCCAUUCAGUCCCUUCCUUCAUUCUUGUCCCUUGUUGUUAGUAGGCUUCUCAGAAUACAGGCAGCAUCGCUUAACGAAGGGGAUCUGUUCUGAGAAAUGCCUCCUUAGGCCAUUGUUGUUCUGUGAACAUCAUAGAGUAUACUUACACAGAUGCAGAUGGUAUAGCCUACUACACACCAAGGCUAUAUGGUAUACUAUCUUGCUUAUAGGCUACAAACCUGUACAGCAUAUUACUGUAUUGAAUACUGUAGGCAGUUGUAACACAAUGGUAAGGAAUUGUUUAUCUAAAGUUAUGUAAACAUAGAAAAGUUACAAUAAAAAUACUAUAUAAAAGAGAAAAAAAUGGUAUACCAGUAUGGGGCACUUGAAUGGAGCUUACAGGACUGAAAGUUGCUCUGGAUGAGUUAGUGAGUGAGUGGUGAGUGAAUGUGAAGGCCUAAGACAUCAUUGCACACUAGUAUAGACUUUAUAAACUCUGUACAAACAGAUACAAUAAAUAUGUAAAAAAUAAAGUAAUUGCAUUACAAUGUUACAAUGGCUAGCAUGUCACUAGGCUAUAGGAAUUUUUCAGCUCCACUGUAAUCUCAUGGGACCAUCGUUGUAAAUAUAGUCCAUUAUUGACUGUAACAUCAUUGCUUGGCUCACUGACUGUAUUUCAUUCCUUUGUCAUGAAGGCAGUUUUCAUUGGCCCUGGAAUCAGGUAAACUUGAACCCGAAUCCUCUUUGACAGUUUAUGAAUUUGUGACUUUGGACAAGUAUAUUAGCCUCUCUGAAUCUUGGUUUUAGCUAUUUAAGAUGGGAAGAAAUCUACUACCUUAUAAUGUUAUGAAGAUUAAACAAAAAGUAUGAAGUGGUAAGCAUGGUACCUAUCAUGUAAGUGCUUAAUAAUAUUUGCUGCUGCUUUUCCCUUAUCCAAUUGUGGAUUUCUUUUAAAAGCGAGAAGCUUGAUUUACAGUUUUAAAAAAAGGCAUUUAUAAGUAUUUUUGAAUUUUUUUUUGUUUUUUUUUUUUUGAGAUGGAGUCUGGCUCUUUUGUCCAGGCUGUAGUGCAGUGGUAUGAUCUCGGCUCACUGCAACCUCUGCCUCCCGAGUUCAAGUGAUUCUUGUGCCUCAGCCUCCCGAGUAGCUCAGAUUACAGGUGUGUGCCACCAUGCCUGGCUAAUUUUUGUAUUUGUGGCAGAGACAGGGUCUCACCAUAUUGGCCAGGCUGGUCUCGAACUCCUGACCUCAGGUGAUCUACAUGCUUCAGCUGCCCAGAGUGCUGGGAUUAUAGGCGUGAGUCACCACGCCCGGCCUGAAAAAAAUUUUUAAAUAUUAAAUACCAAUACUGUAAAUUUGCUAUACUUUAAAAAAUUAUUCUUGCAGAAACUAAAAAAAAACUGACAUUUUCAAGCACUGGUCCAGAUAUUAGUCUUAGUUCACCACUAAAUUAAAGCUCACAGAUGGUAUUAAAGUGUCUCAGAGAUUAUAUCAUUAGAUGAUGUAGGCAACAUAUAUUUUUUCAAAUUGUUAAUGAAUGGAUUUUUUAGACACCUAACAGAUUACAGUUUAGGUAAAGUGCAUCAAAGACAGCAUGGCUACCAAAAUGAAGCAGACUCACAAUGUCUAUUUUAUUUUAUUUCAAAAUUAUAAGCAAAUAUAAGGGAAAAUUUCAUGAACUUUUAAAGACAGAUGGUAGCUCAUCAACGAAUGAAGUGAUAAUAUUCAUAACGUAAACUUCAUAGUGGAGCUGUCAGACUAGUUUAUCUUAAGACCAAAGUUCAAGAUGAUUGAUGUGAUUUGUGUUGCAAUUAUUUGUACAUUUAGAAAUCGUUAUUCUUCAUAGAGAAUAGCACAUUCAGGUUCUAACAUUAUUCUUUUCCCCCACAAACUGGUGGAACCACAAACACCAGUAACAGUGUGUCUCUCUUGUGGGCUCAUCUUGUGCCUCUAAGUUAUUAAUACUGAAGAUGCUCUUGGGAGAUAACAUGUAUUACCCUCAUCUUAGGCAGGAAAAUAGAGGCAUAGAGAAAGGAAAGAAUAUAAUUUUCUUUCCGUGGUCUACUUGUGACAGGCGGGGAAAUGUUAAAGCCUUUCUGACUCACAGGCUCUUUAAUCUUUAACAUGUAUUAUUUAUUGAUUUGCAAAAUGACCCUAAUAUGUAAUAUCAAUACCAGUUUUCUUAUGUUUAUACCGAAAGUGGUUGUGGGUAUGGUAGUAUGUUUUGUGGAAAAGACCAUUAUCAAAAAUGAGGAAGACAGUUGUCUGGCAUGGAUAUUGCCACUGUCCCUUGCUCUGCUCCUGGCAAACAUUGCUGCUUGAUCAUGUCACUACUUCAGAAGCUAGAUUUGACCUCAGCAUCCUUUUUGUUUUUUAAAAAUUUUAAUGUUAAAUUUUUAGUAGAGAUGAGGUCUCACUAUGUUGCUCAGUAUGGCCUUCAACUCCUGAGCUCAAGCGAUCCUUUCGCCUCAGCUUCCCAAACUGUUGAGAUUACAGGUGUGAGCCACUGUGCCCGGCCUCGGAAUCCUUUUCAACAUAUUGCCCAAGGGAGCUAUUACCAGUCAAUCACAGGUCCACAAAACAAAGUUCUUUUUUAGUCUUUCCUUACUGUUGAAUUAAUUUACAUUAAGAGAUUAUGAAUUUACUUAAAAGUUGAGGAUCUAUUAAAUUUGUAGUCCUGUAGCUGGCCUCAAAGUACAGUAUAUAAGACUUAGUUUAUGUUCUCAGCAGGUUUACUUUCCUGUGGGUCAAAUAGACAUGCACACAAUUAGAAGACAAACUCAGCUAUAUUAUUGCUGUGAAGAGAAUAGAGAAUGAUGUAAGAUUAAUUUUAACUGGAAAUGUUGGUGGAUGUGGUGAUUUUGGACUUUGAGGAUAGAAUCUUCCAAGGGGUCUUUAGCAAAGGCAAAGAAGUUAGAAAAUAUAGGAUGGAUUUUGGGCAAUGACAAAUAACGUAUCUUGGCUUAAGUAUAUAACAAGGAUAAGGUAGAAUCAAAUAGAGUAGCUUGCUCCCUGUACAAUGAGUUUUGGGUUUUAUUUUGUUGUUCCUAGUCUCACAGAUGGUUUUUAAUCAGUAGAAUGACGUGAUCCAGAUCUUUGCUUUAAGAAGAUAACUGCUGACAGUUUGAAUAGAAGUAAGGUUGGAAUCUUGACAAAUGUAGGAAUCCUUGGUAGUAGUACAGGAAGAAAUGAUGAGCAUAAGAACUAGAAUUGUGGAAUGGAAGUGGUGAAUUUAGAAUAAAUUUUUAAUGGUAAAAUUAAUGUGAUUCCUACAGGAUUAAGUUAUCCCCAGAGGCUCCAGCAUUUCUUUGGAAGGUUAUCCAGUUAUUUCCUUUGUAUAUUCCAAGUUUAAAAAAUUUUUUAAAGGUGAUUUUUUUUCUCUACUUGUAUUUCUGGAGAAUUAUUUCUUUAUCCUUGGUAUUUCAUUAACUUAAAUAGGAUACGUAUUUGCAUCUGUGAUUUGAUAUAUUUUUUCUUUCCCUCCAUAGAUUUUUUUUCACCUUUAUUUUAGGGAUAUUUUCUAUUAUGUCCUCCUGCCUUUUCUCUUCCAUUUAAUUAGUUAUUCUACUUCAGGGAUACUAAUUAUCUUUCUGUUCAGCCUUUGUCCUACAUUUUCUUUCUAAUUCAAUAUCUUUGUCUUUUUUUUCUCCUCGAUACUUUUUUUUUUUUGAAACAGGGUCUCACUCUUUCAGCCAGGCUGGAGCGCAGUGGCUUGAUCACGGCUCACUGCAGCCUCAACCUCGUGGGCUCAGUUGAUCUUCCCGCUUUAGCCUUCUGAGUAGCUGGGACAACAGGUGUGUGCCACCAUGCCUGGCUAAUUCUUGUAUUUUUUUUGUAGAGAUGAGGUUUUGCCAUGUUGUCCAGGCUGGUCUCACACUCCUGGUCUCAAGUGAUCAACCCACCUUAGCCUCCUCGAUAUACUCUUGUUACCUUAAGAUUUUUCUCCUUGCCAUUUGUUUAAGUCUUUGCUUCUUUUCCUUGCUUUUUUUUUUUUUUCUUUCAAAUUCAUUGUUCUUCUUAAUUGGUUUCCUUAACGCUGAAGCCUUUCUUUUCAAUUUACCUGUUUUGUCUUUUCAUCUUUGGGCUUUUGUUUCAUUAGAUGCAUGUUCUUAUUAGGUUGUUCUGUGUUACAAGAAACUGUUUAUAUGAUUGUAUGGGCAUUUCUUUUUGUCUUGCUCAGGCUUAAUUUGGAUACCUAGGUCAAGACUUCGCUUUUGCCCUUCUGUGGCCCUAUGCUUUCCCAUCUCCUUAGAUUGCGUUAAAUGUCCUAUACCAGUCUCAUUUCAUACUGCUGAGGGUACAGUACAUGUCUAUGGGCUUCAGAUCCUUCCCUCAACUCAGUAUAGGGACUUAGAAGUUGGCAGAUCCUGGUGAUGCCUCUGCCUAGGUUUUGAAGCCUCUGUGCUCGGGAUAUUUUUCCUCAACUUUUGUAGGGCAUGGCAAAUCAAAUUUUUUCUAUCCAAACUAGAGGUAUUUCUUAAAAUUUUCAAGUUUUUUAGUUCACAUUUCUUUCUCACUACUGCUUCCAGGCAGUAAUCAGGCUGCCAGUCAUACUGUACCAUACAGAAUUUUUUUCUGUCCGCUACUUUUUAAACUUUAUAAGUUCUUAGUUUAAAUAGUUUUUUGUAUUACAGUGUGUAACUGAUAGGUUUUCUGCUGAAAAAAACCACAUACACACAAAUAUAUAUAUAUAUCUCUUAGUUGUUGGUAACAGGACGUUCUUUAGUCUUUUUUCACUCUAUACUUGAACAUUUGUACGAUUUUCUAAAUAUUUACUUUUGACAUAAUAACAUGUAUUAUAGGAACUCUACUUCUUAGGCCAGGGUUGACUUGGAAUCAGUUGUUUUAAAAAUAAAAAAAAAUUCUCAUGACUUUAGUAAUUAAGGUUUUUCGAAUGUCUUCUAGCUUUUAUAAAACCAUGUAUUUUUUUAAAAAAAUAAUAUGUUCUUUAAUUACCUUUUAUUUCACUGGCUUUAAGGGAACAGGUGAUUUUUGGCUGCAUGAAUGAAUUGUGUAGUGGUGAAGUCUGAGAUUUUAGUGCACGUGCCACCCGAAUAGUAUACAUUGUACCCUACUACAUUGUGUAGUUUUUAAAAAAUCUCUCAUCCCUCUCCCAUCAUCCCCCUUUCUGAGUCUCCAGUGUCCAUUAUUCCUCUCUGUAUGCCUUUGCAUACCCAUAACUUAGCUCUUAAUUACAAGUAAGAACAUGUGGUAUUUGGUUUUUCAUUCCUGAAUUACUUCAGAAUAAUGGCCUCCAUCUCCAUCCACGUUGCUUCAAAAGAUAUUAUUUCAUUCUUUUUUAUGGCUGAGUAGUAUUCCAUGGUGUAUUUUUUUAAUUCACUCAUUGGUUGAUGGGUACUUAGGUUGGUUCCACAUCUGGCAAUUGUGAAUUUUGCUGUGAUAAACAUACAUAUGCAGGUUUUUUUUUUUUUUGAUACAGUUUUCCUUUGGGUAGAUACCCAGUAGUGAGAUUGCUGGAUCAAAUGGUAGAUUUAGUUCUUUGAGAAAUCUACAUACUGUUUCCCAUAGAGGUAGUACUAAUUUACAUUACCACCAGCAGUACCUAAAUGUUCCCUUUUCAUCACAUCUAUGCCAAUAUCUAUUGUUUUUUGACUUUUUAAUAAUAGCCAUUCUGGCUGGGAUAAGGUGAUAUCUCAUUGUGGUUUUAAUUUGCACGUCCCUGAUGAUUAGUGAUGUUGAGCAUUUUUUUUUCAUGUUUCUUGGUCAUUGUAUACCUUCUUUUGAAAAAUGUUUGUUGAUGUUAUUUGCCCACUUUUUGAUGGGAUUAUUUUUUUCCUUGCAGAUUAGUUGGAGUUCCUUAUAGAUUCUGGAUACUAAUCUUUUGUUAGAUGCAUAGUUUGCAAGUAUUUUCUCCCAUUCUGUGGGUUGUCUGUUUACUCUGAUUAUUUUUUGCUGAGCAGAAGCUUUUUAGUUUAAUUAGGUCUCAUUUAUUUUUUUGUUGCAUUUGCUUUUUGUGUCUUAGUCGUAAAUUCUUUGCCUAGACCAAUAUCCAGAAGAGUUUUUCCUAGGUUUUCUUCUAGCAUUUUUAUGGUUUCAUGCCUUGGAUUUAAGUCUUAAAUCCAUCUUGGUUGAUUUUUGUAUAUGGUAAGAGAUAGGGAUCCAAUUUCAUUCUUCUACAUGUGGCUAUCCAGUUUUCCUGGCAACAUUUAUUGAAUAAGGCGUUCUUUUCCCAAUUUUCAUUUAUGUAUGCUUUGUCAAAGGUCAGUUGAUUGUAUUUGGCUUUAUUUCUGGGUUCUCUACUCUGUUCCUUUGCUCUAUGUAUGUACUUUUAUACCAGUACCAUGCUGUUUUUGUUACUAUAGUAGCCUUGUAGUAUAAUUUGAAGUUGAGUAAUGUGAUGCCUCCAGAUUUGGUUUUUUGUUUAAGAUUGUUUUUUGGUUCCAUAUGAAUUUUAGGAUUGUUUUGUCUAAUUCUGGGAAAAAUGAUGUUGGUAUUUCGAUACAAAUUGCAUUGAAUCUGUAGACUGCUUUGGGCAGCAUGGUCAUUUUCAUGAUAUGGAUUCCUCUAAUGCAUGAGUGUGGGAUGUAUUUCCAUUCGUUUGCAUUGUCUGUGAUUUCUUUCAGAAGUGUUUUGCACUUCUCCUUGUAGAGAUCUUUUACUUCCUUGGUUAAGUAUACCUAGGUAUUUUAUUUUAUUUUUUUGCAGCUAUGGUCAAAGGGAUUGAGUUCUUGAUUCUCAGCUUAGUCAUUGUUGGUAUGCUACUGAUUUGUGUACUUUGAUUUUGCAACCUGUGACUUUACUGGAUUUAUCAAAUCUUGGAAUCUUUUGGAGGAGUCCGUAGGAUUUUCUAGAUAUAUAAUCAUAUCAUUGGCAAACAGAGAUAGUUUGACUUCUUCUUUUCCAAUCUGAAUGCCUUUUAUUUCAUUCUCUUGCCUGAGUGCACUGGCUGUGGCUUUCCAUAUGUUCUUAUUUUUAAAGGAGAGACUUUUACCCAAAAUGAAAAAAUUAUUUGGAUUGGAAAUUGGAAGAAGUACUCUAUUCUUUCAACUUUUAAGAACAAAUGCACCUUAUAGCUCAUGGAAGAAAAAACACAAAUCAAGACAUUUUUGGGUUCCAAGUUGCCAAAGUAUGGAACAAAAUCUGUAAGAAGUACAUUGCAGCCAAUGCCAAAUGGGACACCUGUUAAUUUAUUAGGAACUUCCAAGAAUAGUAAUGUCAAAAGUUACAUCAAAAAUAAUGGCUCUGAUUGUCCAUCAUCUCAUUCAUUUAAUUGGAGGAAAGCAAAUAAAUAUCAGCUUUGUGCACAAGGUGUCGAAGAGCCUAACAAUACUCAAAAUUCACAUGAUAAAAUAAUUGAUCCUGAAAAACGUGUUCCUACUCAAGGAAUGUUUGAUAAAAAUGGGAUAAAGGGAGGUUUGAAAAGUGUUUCUUUAUUCACAUCAAAGUUAGCAAAGCCAUCCACUAUGUUUGUGUCAUCUACAGAGGAGUUAAACCAAAAGUCUUUUUCUGGACCAUCUAAUUUGGGUAAAUUCACCAAAGGCACAUUAUUAGGAAGGACUUCAUAUUCUUCGAUCAAUACUCCAAAAUCACAGUUGAAUGGAUUUUAUGGAAACCGAUCAGCUGGUAGCAUGCAAAGGCCUAGAGCGAACUCCUGUGCCACCAGAAGCAGUUCUGGAGAAAGCUUAGCUCAAUCCCCAGACAGUAGUAAAUCUAUUAAUUGUGAAAAAAUGGUAAGGUCACAAAGUUUUUCACAUUCCAUUCAGAAUUCAUUCCUUCCACCUUCAUCUAUAACCAGAUCACAUUCCUUUAAUAGAGCUGUGGAUCUUACAAAGCCUUAUCAGAACCAACAGCUAUCCAUUAGAGUGCCUCUACGGUCAAGUAUGCUAACAAGAAAUUCCCGGCAGCCAGAAGUACUCAAUGGGAAUGAACAUUUGGGGUAUGGAUUUAAUAGGCCUUAUGCUGCUGGUGGAAAGAAGUUGGCUUUACCAAAUGGCCCAGGUGUAACUUCUACUUUAGGUUAUAGAAUGGUUCAUCCCUCUCUACUGAAAUCUAGCCGAUCUCCAUUUUCUGGGACUAUGACAGUUGAUGGAAAUAAAAAUUCACCUGCUGACACAUGUGUAGAGGAAGAUGCUACAGUUUUGGCUAAGGACAGAGCUGCUAAUAAGGACCAAGAACUGAUUGAAAAUGAAAGUUAUAGAACAAAAAACAACCAGACCAUGAAACAUGAUGCUAAAAUGAGAUACCUGAGUGAUGAUGUGGAUGACAUUUCCUUGUCGUCUUUGUCAUCUUCUGAUAAGAAUGAUUUAAGUGAAGACUUUAGUGAUGAUUUUAUAGAUAUAGAAGACUCCAACAGAACUAGAAUAACUCCAGAGGAAAUGUCUCUCAAAGAAGAGAAACAUGAAAAUGGGCCACCACAGGAUAUGUUUGAUUCCCCCAAGGAAAAUGAAAAAGCCUUCAGUAAAACUGAUGAAUGGAUAGAUAUAAGUGUCUCUGACAGGAGUGAAUGUACAAAACAUACUUCUGGGAAUAAUUUGGUUUCACCAGAUACAGACUACAGAGCUGGUUCUUCGUUUGAACUCUCUCCAUCUGAUAGCUCUGAUGGAACAUACAUGUGGGAUGAAGAAGGCUUGGAACCCAUUGGAAAUGUCCAUCCAGUUGGGAGCUAUGAGUCCUCUGAAAUGAACAGCAUAGAUAUUUUGAAUAAUCUUGAAUCAUGUGACCUUGAGGAUGAUGAUCUUAUGCUUGAUGUGGAUCUGCCUGAGGAUGCACCUCUUGAAAAUGUGGAGUGUGACAAUAUGAACCGCUUUGACCGACCAGACAGAAAUGUUCGGCAGCCUCAGGAAGGUUUUUGGAAAAGGCCACCCCAGAGGUGGAGUGGACAGGAGCAUUACCACCUCAGCCACCCUGACCACUAUCAUCACCAUGGAAAAAGUGACUUGAGCAGAGGCUCUCCCUAUAGAGAAUCUCCUUUGGGUCAUUUUGAAAGCUAUGGAGGGAUGCCCUUUUUCCAGGCUCAGAAGAUGUUUGUUGAUGUACCAGAAAAUACAGUGAUACUGGAUGAGAUGACCCUUCGGCACAUGGUUCAGGAUUGCACUGCUGUAAAAACUCAGUUACUCAAACUGAAACGUCUCCUGCAUCAGCAUGAUGGAAGUGGUUCAUUGCAUGAUAUUCAACUGUCAUUGCCAUCCAGUCCAGAACCAGAAGAUGGUGAUAAAGUAUAUAAGAAUGAAGAUUUAUUAAAUGAAAUAAAACAACUUAAAGACGAAAUAAAGAAAAAAGAUGAAAAGAUCCAACUAUUAGAACUUCAGCUUGCAACUCAGCAUAUCUGCCACCAAAAAUGUAAAGAGGAAAAAUGCACUUAUGCUGAUAAAUAUACCCAAACACCCUGGAGACGAAUUCCUCCUCAAGUACUACAGCCUUCCAGCAGCCUUCCCAGACCCACAGAUCACACCCAGGGAAAACUAAUAAAGCCACAACGUAUCGAGGCCCGCAGUGAAUGCUCAAUCCAAGACAUGCAUCAGGGCGGUGCACAUCCGGAAGAAAGCUUUACACACGUCUUGCACCAAGAAAGCAACUAUGGUUUGGAAGAGCAGCCUUUUUCAUCAGGCCCACAAUUAACAAUGGAUGUGGCUAAGAGUACACCUUCUGAAGCAAACUUAAACAUUACUGUAAAUGCUCAAGAGCCUUAUCAUUUGGCAAACAAUCAAAUUAGUGACAUGCAGUUUAUACCCACUUCUCUUCAGACACCUCCCGAGUCAAGUACAGUAGACCAGGCUAAGAGAGUUGGAAGAAAUCAGUCUCCGCCAGUGGGUUAUAUGUCUCAGCCCAAGUCCUUGCAGCUUUUAAAGCCAUCCAUAUUGAGUUCUUUGGUACCGCCUCCAGUUUCUGAAUCAUCUCCAAGUAGGACUCCCACUUGUAAAAAGUCACCAAUAAUCACAACAUGUAAUUCAGCAAAACUUCAGCCAACAUCUAGUCAAACAAAUCUUGCAAAUAAUCAGAAUCUGAAAGCAUCUAAGCUCCGCCCCCCCUCAGGCUCUUUCAAACAAAAACAAACAAACAGCCCCCAACUAGAGCCUCAAAGCUUCCAGGCCAAGACAAGCAUCCCAAGGCCACUAACACAACGAAAAGAAAUCAUGCAGAAUCCAAAUGGCAAUUUGCAUUCUGGGGAUUGUUUGGCCUCUAAUCGAUAUUCUCGUCUUCCUAAACCAAAGAUACAUUAAGUACAUAGCCAUCACCUGCCAAUUUGUUUCUUAAAAACAAUCUCUUCUGUAAUAGCUUUAUGUGCAGCUUGCAGCUUGCUACUGUGGUGGAGGUUCCAUUGAAAGCCUGCAAAUCUUAAAUUAAAAUGUGGAAGCUUCUACUAGUUUGGCUCCUUCAUUUUAUAUCCUGGUUGAAGUACAUGCCAUUUGAGCAUAAUUAUCUCAGGUAAACACGAAAGUUUGCUUACCCAUUUCAGAGGCCUGCCAAAGGCCCAAAUCAUGUUAUCCAUCCCUCUCCACGUCAGAAAAUUCAUAAUAUUUUACUGAGCAGGCAAGAAGUGUGCUUUGCUGGUUUAGUCCUAUUAAGGUCUGUAUUUAUUGUGGUUGUCAGAACCUCACCCCUUUUCACUUGUCUCUCCUGUGAAUAUGGCUACUAUUUUAACUAAAGAUAUGGUGAUAAUGGAAGAUGGUAGUCUGUAAGCAGAGUUCUGGCCAGUGUUUUGUAUAUUUAAAAGGUCUAUGCAAAAGCUUUGUGAUGAAUAAAGGAGAUUAGGCUUUUAAUGGAAAGUCUAUGUAAGUUUUAUUUUUCCUUGCCAGGGUCAGUCAGCUAAUGUUACUGUUGAUUCAUUUCCCAAAUUCCCCAGACUGAAAGUGUUUCUUAUUACAUAUAAAUCAGUUAUAUAUUCCUUUACAUCUUGUUUUACAAACACAUGUGCAUGCACACACACAUAUACACACACAUACCAUUUAUGUUUGUAUUUGUUACUGGGUAAAUUUUGGAGCGCUUGAGAUACACCUUGAAACCUGUACCUAAAGAUGUAUUCAUUUGUAACAUAUGUUGGUGCUAGAGUUUUGCUGGUAAUUCAGGCUUGAACCCUUAGGCUUGUGGAUCCAUGAUAGCCAUUUUAAGGUUCCACAGCAUUAUGUCUUUAAUUGUAAUAUUUAUAUUUAUUGAUUUUCUGCUAAUAUCUGAAGACUGAAAUAAUGAACUUGAAACAUUUGCACAAAACUUUGAUGGGGUAUAAAUAUACCAUAUAUAGGGAUUGUAAACUAUUUUCUAUAGCAAAACAAGUUAAAAUAUUUUGAGAAAAAUAACAAAUUUAAAUAAGACUAUCUUGAGAAAGCUGGAGUUCAUAAUAUUCUCCCCCUCCCCCAUCUCCAGUCUCCUAGGUUUCCCUUUUCUGUGUUUUUUGUUUUUUUCUGUUUGUUUUUUGAGACAGAGUCUUGCUCCAUUGCCCAGGCUGGAUUACAGUGGCGCAAUCUCGGCUCACUGCAACUUCUGCCUCCCGGGUUCAAGCGAUUCUCCUGCCUCAGCCUCCUGAGUAGCUGGGACUACAGGCAUGUGCCACCAUGCCUGGCUAAUUUUUUUGUAUUUUUAGUAGAGAUGAGAUUUCACCUUGUUGGUCAGGCUGGUCUCGAACUCCUGACCUCAAGUGAUCCACCCACCUCGUCUAUGGUGUAUUUUUGAAAGACAAUUUUUUAAAGGUAGAUUUGGGAAAAAAAUAGAAUUGAAGAUGGGAAAUUUUGUUUUAUUAAAAAGGUGCUAGAAGAUGUUUCAAAGACAAUAUUCUUAUUUUAAUACGCUGUAGAAGGUAGGUGUGGAACCUCCAUGCUACCAUGUGCACAAACCUAAUUAUGCUUUGGGUCACUUGUCAGUUCAGUAAAUCUGCCUUCCUCUUCUCCCAAAUCAUGUCAUCUUUAGGUUGUUCACCUGCAGCUGCUUUAAAUGAAUUAGUAUCUUUCAGAUAGAUAACCUUACAAGGAGAAUGUUUGUUUUGAGCAGCUGACCAAAAAUAUAUCAAACAGGAUUAUGGCCAAAAAGUCACUCAAAUUUCUAGAGAUUCCUUUAAAAGAUGUAUGUUGAUGAAAUUGCCCCUUUAUAAGAAAAACAACAGCAAGUCUUUUAGUAGAAAUUUGAAAGAAGUGUUUGCUACCAUUUUGACCCAUUAUUCCCUUACCUAUCAGAUGAAUUUGCCAUUCACUGGAUAGAAACCAUUCUUGGAUUUGGUAAGAGGUGAGCAAGACAAAUCUUGUACCAUACUCUUAUGUACCAGCACUUCUGAUGGAGAAGCAGUGAAGUUCAGAACGUUCUUCACAUAGUCCAGAUACUGUUAGAGUCAGGCAAAUCAGCAAAGCACUUUGUUAUGGAGAUGACCCAUGAUGGCUGCAGUUGUAAGUGGGCAUACAUGUUCUAUCAUUUUGAAGGAGAAAGAAAACCGUUCUCACAUGUUGCAAAUAUGUGAAUCAUACUAUAUUCCCCUAAAGUAAAACCAGUGACUUAGUGGUUUUUGGUUUAUUUAGAAGUUGGUUUAGACCCUUAUGAAACAUUAUUUACGAGUUGGCCUUAUCCUUAAGGGAAAAGUUCUAAAUUUUUAAAUUUAUUUUUAAUUCCCUAGUCUGAGGGAAAUGUCUUUAUUGUCCAUUACAUAAAAAUGUUGACUCCAGUAAUUUAUUUUUCUCUAUUUUUUCCUCCAUGUAUUUACUCCAUUUUUCUCUAUUUUUUCCUUCCCUGAUGGAUUUGCAGAAAUGUUAACCAAUUAGCUCAACUUUUCUCUACCUUUGUUGAGUCUUAAUCUUUUAGAAGAUAGGCUUAUCGUAUAUUUAUGAAGCAUAAUAUAUUAAAAGAAAACAAAUCUAGGAUGCUUGCAUGACAUAAAGUAUUUGCCUGCAGUUUUCAUUAAAAACUGCAAGAAUAUCAUGCUUGUCUGCUUCUUAGUAAAUGUUAAGUCUGAAAUGGAAGUGAGGAUGUAACUCUACUGAAUAAUCAAAGAUCAUCUUAGAUUUGGCUUGAUCUGUGUUUAUUGCUUCUAUUAAUGUAAAUCAACUCUGUGCCAAAUCCUCCUCCACAAACCAUUUAUUGUCUUAGUUCUAGUGGUAUCAAUGAAGAUAGUUACAGUAUAUGAAUUCUAAGUCCUGAGGAAGAAAUUUUAUGGGGUUUGUUAAGUUUCACAUUCGUGAAAGAGGAAAUUAGUAGAGUAUUCAGACUUUGAUAUUUGGCUGUUAAUGGGAUGCAUAUCAAAUUUUUAAAAGAAGGCUUGGCCUAAGGAGUUUAUUGGUACAGGUGCAGAUGAUUUUAAGGCAUUAAAGGAUUAUAGAGUUAUGUCAUUUAGACUGUUUCUAAUAACUGAGACCAUCUAACAUUUUUCUUUUGGAGUCUCAUUUUUAUUUGUGCAAUAUUUUCAGGCAUAUAGGCUACUGUUCAUUGUAUUUAUAUAUAUAUUAGAAUUUACUAAGUACUUUAACAAGUAAAAAUCUGAAUAUGAAAGAAAAUAUCAGAUUUGCACUUUAAAUGAGCUUAAUUGCUUGAAGUUGUGCCUGAAAUAUCGAAUUGCCUCCUAUUGGGUGUGGCUUUGUUGAAAUAAAUUUGUAAUUGUUGCUGUUUGAAGAUAUCAGUACAGCUGUUCACAGAAAUAUAUUCCCAGCAUGUCACUUUUCCAUUAAAGCACUAAGUUUUCUUUGAAUGUUCCAUUGUUCCGAUAAGUAUUUUACUUUUUUCUCAGUACAUCAGAGAGAGCGUGAUCCCCCUACAGCUGUCACUUCCAAAUGUUCCUGUAGCAUAAAUGGUGUUACAGACACUGAGGUGCACUCUUGGUUUCUGAGCAGAGUUGUCAUACUGGUUUCCUGGUCUCUAGGGCACUGGGGAUGUACUUUGAAAUCACCGAACAGGCUUGCAAUUAAGAUCAAUAAGGCUGCAGCACCAUUUCAAUUUACUUUCCAUCUUACCCAGUAGUUUUUGUGUUUUUAAAUUCGUUUGGGUGGUUAUGUUUGCAUGCUUAAGCACACAUUUGAAAAUUAAUUAUAGCUGUACUACCCGAUGUUUUUCCUUGGGGAUGAUGGCCUUGUUCCUUUUUAAAUUCUGAUGCUUGAAUUCUAUUUUCUAGUGAUUUUUCACAUCUCCCUUUAAGUUUUUGCUGCAGCAAUUUGAGAGAGUACUUUUGAUUAAAUGAUUCUGAUGGUGGGCACCAAUCUACAACUAUGUCAUUAACUGAAGAUACAUGUUUUAAUCUUGUUGGGAAUAAGCUUACCCACUUUCUCCUUGGUAAAGCGUUUACUUAACAAAAUAAUACCCGAGAAUGUAAGGUCUCUAAGUCAUUACUAACAAAGAGCAAAAAUAAUAUCUGCAGUAUUGUUUUUCCCAUUGAUUUUAAGUCAGUUUAGAGUACAAACUGUAUAUUAGAAUUUGCCUGUAAAAUGAAUUCUAAAAAGCAGAUGUAAAGUCUCUCCUGAAAAUGUUGGCAUAGUAAAUAAAAAUAAAGUUCAUAAUUAUAAAA